AACACGCAGGCGCGUCUCCUCAAAUCCUGUCCCUACACCCCUCCUCUUUCUCUUCAUUUCGUUCCCCCUCCUCUUGCAGCACCUCGGCAGGUUCAAACUCUUCUCCGGGAGCGUGGCGGCGAUCGCGAGGUCACGUGAUGAGCAUCCUGCUGCCCAACAUGGCGGAGUUCGACACCAUCUCGGAACUGGAGGAGGAGGAGGAAGAAGAAGCGGCAACGUCGUCGUCGUCGCCGUCGUCGUCGUCGUCGGUAUCUGGGCCCGACGAUGACGAGGAGGAUGAGGAGGAAGAGGAGGAAGAGGAGGAGGAGGAAGAAGAGGAGGAGGAGGAAGAGGAGGAGGAAGCGCCGCCCCCGCCUCGGGUAGUGAGCGAGGAGCAUCUGCGGAGAUAUGCUCCCGACCCUGUAUUAGUGCGGGGUGCCGGCCACAUCACUGUGUUUGGCUUGAGCAACAAGUUUGAUACUGAAUUUCCCUCCGUUCUAACAGGGAAGGUGGCCCCAGAAGAAUUUAAAACCAGCAUUGGCCGUGUGAAUGCAUGUUUGAAAAAGGCUCUCCCGGUCAAUGUGAAAUGGCUGCUGUGUGGUUGUCUCUGCUGCUGUUGCACACUGGGUUGCAGCCUAUGGCCUGUUAUUUGUCUCAACAAAAGAGUGUGGACAUAAAUCCAGAGGGUGAAGUGACUUUCUCAGAAUCACAUGGCAAAUAGCACAGCCACAAAAAUAAUCCUUGCUUUAUUUUGUUUUUGUUUUUGUCUUUAAUACUGCAUCCUCUUGACUACAUCAUGUUUCUUACAUCAAAUUGACUAGUCCUGAGACCAGAAAUGUUUGCGUAAGUUGUAUAAUAAACAGCCCACUGAAUUUUAAUUCUUUAGCAGUGGAUAGAAAACUUUUUCUUAAAGAACCAAAUAGUAAAUAUUUUAGCCUUUGUGAGCCAGAGGUCUCUGUUGCAACCGCUCAACUGUGGCAUUGUCACAUGUAAACAGCCAUAAGCAUAUGUAAAUGAGUGAGCAUUACUGUGUUCUCAUAAAACUUUAUUUACAAAAACAGGCAGCAAGCCAGAUCUGGCCUAUGGGCUGUUGUUUGACACCUUGCUCUAGCCAUCUCUAAUUGGGUAUCUAGCUUUAUGGAAGUCAUAUCUCUGUUUGCUCACAAAAUAAAAUGGAAAUAAUAAUGAAGAUGCUAUAUUAGCCAAUUAUUGAAAAUAUUUCCAGCAAAAGAAUUUUUAUGUAGAUAGUCUGCCUUAUAAUUUUUUGGCAGUAUAAUUCAUGAGAAUUUUCUCUAGCAAAUUAGGUGAUAAAGAAAUAUAGGUCAGAGUGCCUUGAGUUCCCCCUAAUCUCUCUUGACUCUGGUGCGAUUUCGCAGCUACAUGAUACAUUAAGUGAGGCUUUUCAUUUACUUGUUCUUCUAUCUACCACUGAACCAACUGUGAUAUCAUAGUCAAUUUCAGCCCCAGUCAUGCUAUGACUCAAAAUUUGAAAUUACUUUUAUCCUUUCCUUUUUUGCUUUGAUACUCAUUAAAUUGAGAGAGAUGGUCAGAGGAAAGGACUACUUUCUGACUCAUGACAUAAAUAUGAUGUUUUAGGAGAUAGAGGUUAUAAUUCACUGUCCUGUUUGAUUCUGUGUUUUUGUAGCUAAUUAUAAAAAGAAGGAAAAGCAUAUGAUAGAAACAAAUGCCCCAUCCAUACAUUAUGCCAUUUGGAAAAGAAAAUCAGUCUUUGCAAUGAGAGACAAAUAGUUCUGCCAAGAAUUAAGCAAAUUACGUGUAAUCUAUGUAUAAUUUAGGCCUUUCAUAAAAUACGUUUUGUGCUCUUGGGCAAAGACAACAUGCAUAAAGUGAGUGCAUAGAGUAUUAUAACUUGGUCAUAGACUGCCUUUUCCUUACUGUCUUUGAACCUUUUAAUUUAUGUGUCAACCUUGAGUCAUUUGAGCCAUAUAUAAGAAAAUGAUGUUUAUGGCAUGUUAAUACUAAAAGCUGAUAAGUUUGCUUCCUUUUUUGUUAGCUUUACUGGCUAAUUGUAUUGAAUGUAGGAUUGUAUCUGCUCUGCAGAAGUACAGUGAUUGGUAUUAAGCUAACUUUGAUACUUUUCUGGUCAGCUUGAGAGUCAGCCAUCUGGUUUAAAAAAUAAUUUAUUGGGAAAUAAUUUACAGAACAUAAAGUUAACUCAUAUUAAGAGAACAAUUCAUUGAAUAUUAUUGUACUUACAGAGUUGUGUAACUAUCACCAUAAUCUAAUUUUAGAACAUUUCCAUCAUCCUAAGAGUAAACCUUGUGAUCACUUUUUGUCACUCCCAAUUUCCCUCCAAUCCUCCCAGCCCUAUACAACCACUGAUCUACUUUCUCUCUUAUGUUUGCAUUUUUGAACAUUUUAUAUGAUAUGUACUCUUUCAUGGCUUUUAAAACUGAACAUAAUGUUUUUUGUGGAAAAAUACACGACAUAAAAUUUGCAUUUUUAACCACUUUAAAGUGGAUAAAAUUCAGUCGCAUUAACUACAUUGACAGUGUUAUGCAACCAUCCACUAUCUAGUUUCAGAAAUCUUUUAUCACCUGCAAGGAAAAUCUCAUAUCCAUUAAGCAGUCAUUUCUCAUUUUCCUUCCCCUCAGGAAGUUAAAAAGUGUUUCCCUCUUUUCUGUAUUUUACAAAAGUUUAAGAAGGAUUGGUAUUCUUCUUUUAAACAUUUGGGAGAAUUUCCUUUCUUUUGGGCAUAACAGUGACACUAUCUGAUCUUGAGUUUUUUUUCUUGGUAGGUUUUUGAUUACACAUUCAAUAUUUACUUGUUAUAGGUCUAUUCAGAUUUUCUAUUUCUACUUGAGUCAAUUCUAGGAGUUUGUUCAUUUCGUCUAGGUUGUAGGCCUACAAUUAUUUUUAGUAUUCACUUCUAAUUUUUUUCUAAAUUACUGUAAGAGUGAUAUGUAAUGUCCCUAUUUUCAUUUCUGAUUCUAGUCAUCUCAGUCUUCUUUUUUUUCUUAAUCCUUGUAGCUGAAAGUUUGUCAAAUUUCUUUUCAAAGAAAAAACUUUUGGUCUUGUUCAUUUUUUCUGUUGUUCUAUUCUGUAUUUCAUUUCUCUCCACUCUAUUUUUUCCUUUUUUCUGCUAUGUUUGGGUUUAGUUUGCUCUUUUUAGUUCCAUAAGGUCUAAAUUUAGGUUAUUGAUUUGAGAUCAUUCUUCUUUCUUAAUGUAGGCAUUUACCGCCCUCAGUUUUCUUUGAAACAUUGCUUACUCACAUUCUGAGAUACUGGGAGUUGUGAUUUCAUUGUAUGAAUUUUGAGGGAAUAUAAUUCAGCCCAUAACACAUAAGGAAGGACUUCCACUAUUUUGCUAUUUGUUUUCCAUGUCGUAUGUUUUUUGUUCCUCAAUUCCUUCAUUACUUAUUUAUUUUAUGUUUAAUUGAGUUUUUUACUGUACUGUAUACCUUAUUUCCUUUUCUGUAUCUUUUUAAGUUAUUUUCUUAGUUGUUACAAUUAACAUCUUAAACUUAUAACACACUAGUUUGAAUUAAUAUCACCUUAGCUUUAAUAGUAUGUAAAUUCUACUGCUAUGUAUAUCUAUACCUCCCCUUUUAUGUUGUUGUUAUCACAAAUUAUAUGUUAUAUAUUGUGUGUCCAUUAACAGAUUUAUGAUUAUCAUUUUGUCUUUUAAUCAUACGGGAAAAAGAGUUCCAACCCAAAAAUACAAUAUUGGCUUUUAAAUAUAUUUGUGCAGUUACCUUUACCAGUGUUCUUUAUCACAUGCCUCAAGUUAUUGUCUAGUGUCCUUUCAUUUCAGCCUAAGGAUCUCUUUUUAGAAUUUAUUGAAAAGCUGUCCUAAUAGUGAUGAACUCCCUCAGCCCUUGGUUGUCUGGGAAUUUCUUCAUUUCUUUUUUUGAAGGAUAAUUUUGCUCAGUAUAGAAUUUUUGGUUGACAGUUUGCUUGUUUGUUUUGUAAUUUCUGCACUUUAAAUACUAUAUGCCAUCCCACUGCCUCUGACCUUCAUGGUUUCUGAUGUGAAAUUAACUGUUAAUCUUAUGGAGAGUCUCUUGUACUUAACAAGUCACUUCUUUCUUACUGCUUUCAAGAUUUCCCUCUUUGUUUUUUACUUUCAACAGUUUAAUUAUACUUUAUCUUGGUAUGGUUCACUUUGAGUUUAUCCUACUUGGAAUUUAUUUGGCUUCUUGGAAUGUUUUUUUUCUGUGUGCAGUUUCAAAUUAAUAUCUGGUGUCACUUGAUGCCAGCCUGAAGAACUUCUUUUAGUGUUUCACAUAAGCUGGGUCUGCAGGCCACAGAUACUCUCAGUUUUUAUUUAGGAAUGUCUUUAUUUUGUCUUCACUUUUUAAUAUGCAAUUUUUAAUUAAUAGAUUUUUAAAAACAAUUUUAGGUUUACAGAAAAAAAAAUGAGCAAAAAGCACAGAUUCCAUAAACCCCCUCAUCCAAUACCAAUUUCCCCUACUAUUGAGAUCUUACAUUAGUGUGGUACAGUUGUUACAAUUGAUGAGCCAAUAUUGAUAUAUUAUAAUUAACUAAAGUCCAUGGUUUACAUUAGGCUUCACUCUUUGUGUUCUACAUCCUAUGGAUUUUGGCAAGUGUAUAAUGAUAUGUAGCCAUCAUCAUAGUAUCGUACAGAAUAGCAGUUUCACUGCCCUAAAACUCCAUUAUGCUACACCUAUUUCAUCCCACCCGCAUAUCCUGAGCAAUCACCUAACUUUUUAUUGUCUCCAUAGGUUUGCCUUUUCCAGAAUGUCAUAUAAGUUGAAAUUAUAUAGAAUAUAUUCAUAUUGGCUUCUUUCACUUACCAAUAUGCAUUUAAGGUUCCUCCAUGUCUUUUCCUGGCUUGAUAGCUCAUUUCUUUUUAUCACUGAAUAAUAUUCCAGUUUUGAGAUUUGCCAGUUUAUCUGUUCACCUAUUAAAGGGUUUCUUGGUUACUUCCAAGGUUUCACAAUCAUAAAUAAGACUGUUAUAAACAUUCAAGUACAGGUUUUUGAGUGGACAGUUUUGAACUCAUUUGAUGAUUGCUGGAUCAUGUGGUAAGAGUAUGUUUAGUUUUGUAAGAAACUGCCAAACUGUCUUGCAAAGUCGCUGUGCCAUUUUGUAUUCCCACCAGCAAUGAAUAAGACUUCCUGUUGUUCUACAUCUUCAUCAACGUUUGGUGUUGUCAGUAUUGUGGAUUUUGGCCAUUCUAAAACGUAGGUAGUGAUAUCUCACUAUUGUUUUAAUUUCUAAUUCUGCAUAGUCAUACGAUAUUGAGCAGCUUUUUACAAGCUUAUUUUCCUUCUAUGUAUCUUCUUUGAAGAGGUUUCUGAUCAGGCCUAUGACCCCCCUUUUUUUAAUGACAUGGGUACAGGAUGGUUCCUGAAGGAAAAGAGGGCUUAGUGGCCUCCAAAUUCCCUCACUCACCAAUUUCUGGAGGAGACUCUAGUGGGGUGAGGACUGAGGAGCCUAUGCACACUUUUUCAUUGGGUUGUUUAUGUUAUUAUUGUUGAGUUGUUAAAGAGUUAUUUGUAUACUUUGGAUACCAGUUUUCUACAAAGUAUGUGUUUUGCAAAUAUUUUCUCUCAGCCUGUGGUUUGUCUUUUUACUCUCUUAAUAGUAUAUUUUGUAGAGUGGAACAUUUUAAUUUUAAUGAAUUUCACCUUAUUAAUGUUUUCUUUUAUGCAUCUUGCUUUCUGGUGUUGUAUGUAAGAAUUCAUUGCCAAACCCAAGGUCACCUAGAUUUUGUUUUAUGUUAUAUUCUAGGAAUUUUAAGAGUUUGGCAUUUGUGAAAGGUGUAAGGUAUGUGAAUACAUUCAGUUUUCCUUGCAUGUUGAUGUCCAUUUGUACCAGCACCAUCUGUUGAAAAGACAACAAUUUCCUUGAAUUGCCUUUUUGUCAGAGGUCUAUUUCUGCCUUGUCUAUUCUGUUCCAUUGAAUAACUAAUCAGUUCUUUCACCAAUUCCACACUAUCUUGAUUACUGUAGCUUUAUAGUAAGUCAUGAGGUCAAGUAGUAUCAGUCCUCUUUGUUCUCCUUAAAUACUGUGUUGACUAUUAUGGAUCUUUUACUUUUCCAUAUAAACUUUAGAAUCAUUUUUUCAAUAAUCACAAAACAUUGUGAUUUUGCAUUCUGAAACUUUACUGAAGUUUUUUUUUUAAUCAGUUCAAGGAGCCUUUUGGCAGAGUCUUUUGGGUUUUUCUAGGUAUAAAAUAAUACCAACAGCAAAAAGAGGUAGUUUCACUUUUUUACCUAUUUAUGUGCCUUUUAUUUUUUUGUCUUGACUGAUUGCUCUGUCUAGGACUUCCAGUACUGUGUUGAAUAGGAGUGGUGGGAGUGAGUAUCCUUUUCUUGUUCCAGUUCUCAAAAAGGCUGGGGAAAUGGUUCCAGCUUUUGCCUGUUCUAUAUGAUGUUAGCUAUGGGUUUGCCAUAGAUGGCUCUUAACUAUUUUGAGAUAUAUUUCUUUGAUGGCUAGUUUGUUAAGGGUUUUUAUGAAGUGAAAUUGGGUUUUAUCAAAGGCUUUUUCUGUGUCUGUUGACAUGAUUAUAUGGUCUUUGUUUUUUGUCCUGUUUAUGUGGUGAAUCACAUUUAUUGAUUCGCAUAUGUUGAACCAACCUUGUAUCCUAGGAUUAAAGCCUACUUGAUUGUGGAGAAUUAAUUUUUUGAUGUGCUGCUGGAUUCAGAUUGCUAGUAUUUGUUGGGGAUUUUUGUGUCUAUGUUCAUCAGGGAUAUUGGCCUGAAGUUUUUUUUUCAUUGUGUCGUUGCCAUAUUUUGGUAUCAGGAUGAUGCUGGCUUCAUAGGAUGAAUUAAGGAGGAGUCUCUCCUCCUCUAUUUUUUGGAAUAAUUUUAGUAUGAUUGGUAUUAGCUCUUCUUCGUACUUCUGGUCGAAUUCAGCUGUGAAUCCAUCUGGUUUAGGGUUUUUCUUCAUUGGUAGGUUUUUAAUUGCUGUUUCAAUUUUGGAACGUGUUAUUGUUCUGUUCAGGGUUUCCAUUUUUUUUUCCUGAUUCAAUCUUGAGAGCCUGUGUGUUUGCAGAAAUUUAUUCAUUUCCUGUAGAUUUUCUAAUUAGUAUGCAUAGAGGUGUUCAUAAUAAUGUCUGAGGAUCUUUUAUAUUCCUGUGAGAUUGGUUGUAAUGUCUCCUUUGUCAUUUCUCAUUGUGCUUAUUUGGAUCAUCUCUCAAUUUUCUUUGUUAAUUUAGCUAUCAAUCUACAGAUCUUGUUUAUCCCUUCAAAAAACCAACUUUUGGUUUCAUUGACCCUUUGUAUGGAUUUUGGGGUCUCAGUUCCUUUCAGUGCUCCUCUGAUUUUUGUUUUCUUCUGCUAGCUUUGUUAGUUUGUUUUUGUUUUUCUAGUUCCUCUAGGUGCAAUGUUAGAUUGAUAAUUUGAGAUCCUUCUAAGUUUUGACUGUAGGCAUUUGGCACUGUAAACUUUCCUCUUCAUGCUGCUUUUGCUGCAUCCUAGAGAUUUUGUGUUUUGUGGAUGAUUGUCUUGUAUAGUAUCAUGGAGAGGUUCUCUGAAUUUCUUGAAUUUGCAUGUCGACCUCUACCAAGAUUAGGGAAAUGUUCAUGGACUGUAUCCUCAAAUAUGUUUUCCAUGUUGCUUACUCUGUCUCCUUCUGUCUCAGGAGUCCUAAUGUGUCAUAGGUUUGGUCUAUCUACAUAAUUCCCUAUUUCUCAGAGACUUUGUUCCUUUUUUAUAAUUCUGUUUUCUUUAUUUUUGCCUGACUGGCUUGAUUGAAAAGGCCAGUCUUCAAUCUCUGAAACUCUUUCUUGAGUUUGAUCUAAUCUUUUUAAUGCUUCUAAUUUUAUGUUGAAAUUCCUGUAGUGAAUUUUUCAAUUCCAGAAGUUCAGUUUGGUGCUUUUUUAAUAUGGUCAUUUCAUCUUUCAAUUUUUGGAUCAUUUUACUGGCUUCCUUGGAUUGGACUUCAACUUUCUCUUGAAUCUCUUUGAAUUUCUUUGCCAUCCGAUUCUGAAUUCUAUGUCAUUUCAGACAUUUCAAACUGUUUAGGAUCCAUUUCUGGGGACAUAGUGCAAUCAUUGUUAGAUAAGUAAACACACUGACUUUUUGAAUUGCUGGAGUUAUUGCAUUGAUUUUUUUUUCUGCUCUGGGGGUUCUUGUGUUUCUCAUUUUGAAAUUGCUAUUAUUUGGAUGGGACUUUUUUAUUUUAUAGGGGUUUUUUUUCCCUCUUGAAGGUUUGACUGGUGAAUGUUGUGUACAGGUGCUUUCCUUUGUUUUGUUUUGUUUUGUUUUGUUUUGUUUUGUUUUGUUUUGUUGAGGCAGAGUCUCGCUCAGUCACCCACGCUGGAAUACAAAGGCAUGAUCUCAGCUCACUGCAAUGUCUGCCUCCUGGGUUCAAGCAAUUCUUCUGCCUCAGCCUCUCCAGUAGCUGGGAUUACAGGCACCUGCUAUCA